AAAGCUACCUUAUAGUGAUUUUUAUAUUUAAAAUAUAUUAAUUAAUGGUCUUAUGGUUGUAUAGAAGAAUGUCCCUCUAAUUAGGAAGCACGUGCUAAAAUAUUUAGGGGUCAAGUGUCUUCAUGUCUGUGCUUUCAAAUGGUUCUAGAUAAAAUGAACAUGUCAGAAUGCUAAUAAUUGAUGAAUAUAAUUAUGGAUGUCCUGGUGAUUAUUAUACGUUUUUUCAACGUUACUGUAUGUUUGAAUUUUUUAAUAAUAAAUUUGGGGUCUGGGCACAGUGGCGGUAAUUCCAGCACUUCCGGAGACCAAGGUGGGAGGAUCACUUGAGUCCAGGAGUUGAGCCUGGGGAAUAUAGUGAGACCCUGUCUCUAAAACAAAACAAAACAAAACAAAACCAAAAAAAAAAACAUACUAGCCGGGCAUGGUGGCUAGUCCCAGCUACUUGGGAGGCCGAGGUGAAAGGAUCACUUGGGCCUGGGAGGUCAAGGCUGUAGUGAGACAGGAUCACGCCACUGCAGUCCGGCCUGGGCAACACAGUAAGACCCUGUCUCAAAAAAAAAUUAUUAAUAAGAUGGGCACAGUGGCUCAUGCCUGUUAUCCUAGCACUUCAGGAGGCCGAGUUGGACAGAAAGCUUGAACCCAGGAGUUCAAGACCAGCCUGGCCAACAUGGUAAAACCCCGACUCUACUAAAAUUACAAAAAUUAGCCAGGUGUGGUGGUGUGUGCCUGUAGUCCCAGCUACAGAAAAGGCUCAGGUGGGAGGAUCGCUUGAGCCCUGGAGGCAGAGGUUGCAGUGAGCCAAGAUUGCACCACUGUACUCCAGCCUAGGUGACAGAGUGAGACUCUGUAUUAAUAAUUAUUAAUAAUAAAUUUGGAGGAAGAGUACUAUAAGAGACAACAAUAUUUUUUAAUAAAGAUAUAUAUAUGUACCUUUAUUGAAAAACUUAGAGAAUAAUUGCAAAGAUGUUCUUGGGUCUAAGUACAUCAUGAUCAUCGGGUACUUUACAGAGAACACUGAAGUCAGGAUGUGAAAUCUGCUGUUAUUAAAUCCAAGCAGACCUGAGAUCCCCUUCCCUGAUUAAUAGUACCCACCAAUCUUUGUGGUAUUACUGGUUUGUGGAUCACUCUCAAGUAAGAGGUCUUCAAUGCUAUUUUUGGAGAUUUUUGUUUUCAAAAAUCAUUCUGCAUUCUUUGCUUUAUGAUUAUGGCUAAAAUAAAUUUCAGAGGUCACCUAGUUUUUCAGUCUGUUUUAGAGUAAGGAACUAUAAGGUUCUUGCAGAAAUUUCAUUUUAAGAGAAAAGAGGGGGGAAGUGCUGCUGGUUAACAAUGAACAUGUUUGUACCAUUAUAAAAUUGAUUCAAUUUUAAAUUCCCACCACUUGUAGAGAAUACUGAGGACUGCAGCUGAUUUAUAACUUUUGCUAAUUAAUAUGUUACAUGAGCAGGCCGGGCACAGGGGCUCAUGCCUGUAAUCCCAGCACUUUGGGAGGCUGAGGCAGGUCAGGAUCAACUGAGGUCAGGAGUUUGAGACCAGCCUGGCCAACAUGGUGAAACCUCGUCUGUACUAAAAAUACAAAAAUUAACCAGACAUUGUGGUGCUUGCCUAUAGUCCUUGCUACUGGGGAGGCUGAGGUGGGAGAAUCACUCGAACCUGGGAGGCGGAGGUUGCAGUAAGCCGAGAUCGUGCCACUGCACUCCAGCCUGGGCGACAGAGUAAGACUCCCUCCCUCCCCCAACCCCCCAAAAAAAUAGCCAGGCACGGUGGCUCAUGCCUGUAAUCCCAGCACUUUGGGAGGCUGAGGCUGGCAGAUCACCUGAGGUCAGGAGUUCAAGACCAGCUUGACCAACAUGGAAAAACCCUGUCUCUACUAAAAAUACAAAAUUAGCCAGGUAUGGUGGCACAUGCCUGUAAUCCCAGCUACUUGGGCUGAGGCAGGAAAAUCACUUGAACCUGGGAGGCGGAGGUUGCAGUGAGCCGAGAUCGCGCCAUUGCACUCCAGCCUGGGCAACAAGAGCGAAACUCUGGCUCAAAAAAAAAAAAUUGUUACAUGAGCUAUGGAGAAAAAGAACAGGAAAGGUAUAGUGGUGAGGUUAAGGGGUUGGGUGAUGGACGGCCUCAAUGAGAAGGUAAUGUAACUGGAGCAAAGACCUAAGGAUAAGAGGGGAGUAUCUUCAUAGUUAAAUUAACUUUAUCAAAAUAAACUGUAUCAACAGUAUAAACCAGAGAAACAUAAUUAAGUAUUUUAUGAUGUUAAAACAAAAGUUAACACUUUGAAAAUUUAAAAUUAUAACUUUAUGAAGUACACAUGUAGAGGUGCGUGAUAUUAGCACUAUUAUUAGGCCAUGAAUUUAAAUUUUUUUGUUGCUUAUCAAUUUAGCAAAUGUUUAUCAAUUUAUGCUAUUUGUAGGACUUUUUUCUGCGUUUUUAGACUCUUAAAAAAUACUACAAUGUUAAAAUAGCAAUAAAAGUGACCAUACAUGUUAAGUAUAUUUUCUCUGCAAUUAUUUGGUUCAGUUUUAAUUUUAUCUGUAACAAUGAUAGUAAUUGCUGUUUCACUUUCUCUCUUCUGUGAUGUUGUUUCCUCUGAAUGUAUGAGCUGCUUUACUCCUAAGUUUGCUGACAUUGUUGCAAAUGCUUAUCAGAAUGAAUCCUAUAUUUUUAUUUAAAAUGAUCGUGUCAUUUUCAAUCAGGCAGCCCAUCCAAACAUGCGGACCUAUUAUUUCUGCACUGAUACAGGAAAGGAAAUGGAGUUGUGGAUGAAAGCCAUGUUAGAUGCUGCCCUAGUACAGACAGAACCUGUGAAAAGAGUGGACAAGAUUACAUCUGAAAAUGCACCAACUAAAGAAACCAAUAACAUUCCCAACCAUAGAGUGCUAAUUAAACCAGAGAUCCAAAACAAUCAAAAAAACAAGGAAAUGAGCAAAAUUGAAGAAAAAAAGGCAUUAGAAGCUGAAAAAUAUGGAUUUCAGAAGGAUGGUCAAGAUAGACCCUUAACAAAAAUUAAUAGUGUAAAGCUGAAUUCUCUGCCAUCUGAAUAUGAGAGUGGGUCAGCAUGCCCUGCUCAGACUGUGCACUACAGACCAAUCAACUUGAGCAGUUCAGAGAACAAAAUAGUCAAUGUUAGCCUGGCAGAUCUUAGAGGUGGAAAUCGCCCCAAUACAGGGCCCUUAUACACAGAGGCCGAUCGAGUCAUACAGAGAACAAAUUCAAUGCAGCAGUUGGAACAGUGGAUUAAAAUCCAGAAGGGGAGGGGUCAUGAAGAAGAAACCAGGGGAGUAAUUUCUUACCAAACAUUACCAAGAAAUAUGCCAAGUCACAGAGCCCAGAUUAUGGCCCGCUACCCUGAAGGUUAUAGAACACUCCCAAGAAACAGCAAGACAAGGCCUGAAAGUAUCUGCAGUGUAACCCCUUCCACUCAUGACAAGACAUUAGGACCCGGAGCGGAGGAGAAACGGAGGUCCAUGAGAGAUGACACAAUGUGGCAGCUCUACGAAUGGCAGCAGCGUCAGUUUUAUAACAAACAGAGCACCCUCCCUCGACACAGUACUUUGAGUAGUCCCAAAACCAUGGUAAAUAUUUCUGACCAGACAAUGCACUCUAUUCCCACAUCACCUUCCCACGGGUCAAUAGCUGCUUAUCAGGGAUACUCCCCUCAACGAACUUACAGAUCGGAAGUGUCUUCACCAAUUCAGAGAGGAGAUGUGACAAUAGACCGCAGACACAGGGCCCAUCACCCUAAGCAUGUCUAUGUGCCUGACAGAAGGUCAGUGCCAGCUGGCCUGACUUUACAGUCUGUUAGUCCCCAGAGCCUCCAAGGGAAAACGCCAGAGGAGCUUACGCUGCUGCUAAUAAAGCUGAGACGGCAGCAAGCCGAACUGAGUAGUAUCCGGGAGCAUACGUUAGCACAGCUCAUGCAGCUAAAGCUUGAGGCCCACAGCCCAAAGAAUGAAAUUCUUUCACAUCAUCUCCAAAGGAACACCAUAUAUUUGGAUCAUCAGAUGAAAGAAAAUGAACCUAUUAUCACCAUGGUUCACACAAUGAUUGAGAACUCGGCGCUAAGACCCCAACUGUACCAGCAAUUCUUAAGACAGAAGAGCAAGAUAAGUCUAUAUUGUCUGUCACAAGAUGAAGGUAGAGGCACAUUAUACAAAUACAGACCUGAAGAAGUAGAUAUUGAUGCCAAGUUAAGCCGAUUAUGUGAACAAGAUAAAGUGGUGCAUGCUCUGGAAGAGAAACUUCAGCAACUCCACAAGGAGAAAUACACGCUUGAGCAAGCUUUGCUAUCAGCCAGCCAAGAGAUAGAAAUGCAUGCAGAUAACCCAGCAGCCAUUCAGACAGUGGUGUUACAAAGGGAUGAUUUACAAAAUGGACUGCUUAGUACGUGUCGAGAACUUUCUCGAGCCACUGCCGAAUUGGAACGAGCAUGGAGAGAAUAUGAUAAGUUAGAAUACGAUGUAACUGUUACCAGGAACCAGAUGCAAGAGCAGCUGGAUCACCUUGGUGAAGUUCAGACGGAAUCAGCAGGAAUUCAGCGUGCACAGAUUCAGAAAGAACUUUGGCGAAUUCAGGAUGUCAUGGAAGGGCUGAGUAAACAUAAGCAGCAAAGAGGUACUACAGAAAUAGGUAUGAUAGGAUCAAAGCCUUUCUCAACAGUUAAGUACAAAAAUGAGGAAGAGGAAGUAGUCCCACCUCGUCCUCCACUUCCUCGGUCCUAUGACUUUACAGAGCAGCCUCCCAUAAUCCCCCCUCUGCCCAGUGAUAGCAGCUCCUUGCUCUGUUAUAGCAGGGGCCCAGUUCAUCUGCCUGAAGAAAAGAAGAUGUAUCAAGUUCAAGGAUAUCCAAGAAAUGGAUCUCACUGUGGUCCAGAUUAUAGACUCUACAAGAGUGAACCAGAGUUAACAACAGUGGCAGAAGUUGAUGAAUCUAAUGGAGAAGAAAAAUCAGAACCUGUUUCAGAGAUAGAAACUUCAGUUGUUAAAGGUUCCCACUUUCCUGUUGGAGUAGUCCCUCCAAGAGCAAAAUCACCAACACCCGAAUCUUCGACAAUAGCUUCCUAUGUAACCUUGAGGAAAACUAAGAAGAUGAUGGAUCUAAGAACGGAAAGACCAAGAAGUGCAGUGGAACAGCUCUGUUUGGCUGAAAGUACUCGACCAAGGAUGACUGUGGAAGAGCAAAUGGAAAGAAUAAGAAGACAUCAACAAGCGUGCCUGAGGGAGAAGAAAAAAGGGUUAAAUGUUAUCGGUGCUUCAGACCAGUCACCCUUACAAAGCCCUUCAAAUUUAAGGGAUAAUCCAUUUAGGACUACUCAGACUCGAAGGAGGGAUGAUAAGGAACUGGACACUGCCAUUAGAGAAAAUGAUGUAAAGCCAGACCAUGAAACUCCUGCAACAGAAAUUGUUCAACUAAAAGAAACCGAACCCCAAAAUGUGGACUUCAGCAAAGAGUUAAAAAAAACUGAAAACAUUUCAUAUGAAAUGCUUUUUGAACCUGAGCCAAAUGGAGUAAAUUCUGUGGAAAUGAUGGAUAAAGAAAGAAACAAAGACAAAAUGCCUGAGGAUGUUACAUUCAGCCCUCAAGAUGAAACACAGACCGCAAAUCAUAAACCAGAAGAGCAUCCUGAAGAAAAUACAAAGAACAGUGUUGACGAACAGGAAGAAACUGUUAUUUCUUACGAAUCAACUCCUGAGGUUUCUAGAGGAAAUCAAACAAUGGCAGUGAAAAGUCUGUCCCCAUCUCCUGAGUCCUCGGCAUCGCCAGUUCCAUCCACUCAGCCGCAGCUCACAGAAGGAUCACAUUUCAUGUGUGUGUAGUCUUAGAAGAACUAUACUGACUUCUGUUGAAACCAUUCAAAGCUAAAGACAUGGACCUUCAGCAGUGUAAGAAGAUAUUGUACAGUAUAUUUUAAAUCUAUGAAAUUCAUAGUUCUGAUGCUUUUGGUCACAGAGCAUCAUUUUAUCACUUCUGGAAAAUGUUUAUUCCAAAACAGCUUUAAUGGCCCAUAUGUACACUUCGUAAUCUCAAGGUUAUUAUUCUGACACCAGCUUGCUGCUAUGAUUUCAGAGCACAUAAGUAAAGGUGCUUUUUAAUGUGCAGUCUAUUUCCAGAGCUUACUUAGUUGCUGAUUUCCAGAUUUCGAUGUUUCUUAAGUCUAGGUGAAUUUAUAUAUAUAUUUUUUUGCUUUUCAUUUUCUAAAGUUAGUUAUUAUUUCCAUUGAAGCUUGUUUUCUUUUUUUUCUUCCCAUUUUAGCUACUGCAGUGCUUUUGUUUCACACUUGAUUUGUAAAAAUUUUAUAUAUAUGUAUUUAAAAUGUGCCAUUUUAUUGCUAAGUGAAGUAUGUCCUGUUUUCUGCUAUAAUUCUUUCUCGGUCAGAUUGCAAUGUCAGCAGUUACUGCCACACUCCUGUCAGCUUAAACACAAAUGUUACUGCUUAUCUUUUCUUAAAAAAAAAAAAAACAAAGUGUAGGUAUUUUGAAGUACUGGGCUUAUAUUUCAUUGGAAUACAUGUGUACAGCAAUAAGCAGGUUUCCAAAUCCGGUACUUAGUUUGUGUACAAAUGUAAUUAUGUUCAUUGUGUAUAUAUUAUACAAUGAGCACAUGUAAUGUAUUAAAGGCUACUUACUAUUGUUUAAAUGCAAAUGUUCAUAUCUCAUUUCUUUUUUUAUCAUGUUAAAUAAAUGUUGAUGUUCUUAAA